GUGUAGCGGCUAUGGGCGCUGUCUUACAACAAAGCCAAGGAAUCUCGCUGCUGAGGGCAGUUCUGUGCUUUAUUAUGAAGAAUAAUGGACGAUGAUGAUGCAAAGCUCAAAGCAGAAAUAGAAGCUGAAUUGGAUAAACUCAGCAUUUCCUCCUUGGAAAAAGAAGACAUUGAGAGUGAUGCAAAAUCAGAAACCCAGAGUGAUGAUAGUGAUACAGAUUCAGUUGAAUUACCAGAAUCAGUUCUUCACUGUAUUAACAUCAUAAAGAACAGGAGUAAAGCUGUUGAAGAGCUCAUUCUUCAGGACCUGGAAGAUACUGAUAUUUUAAGCUGUAGUUAUGGAGCAGUUUCUAAUAAUCAUAUGCAUUUAAGAACAGGACUAUCAACUGAAUAUGAAGAAAGUUCAGAGCAAUUAAUUAAGAUAUUAUCUGAAAUAGAAAAAGAAGAAUUUAUGAGAAGUAAAACCGAUUGUGCCACUCCUGAUUUUGUUCCUGAGCCUAGUCCUCAUGACUUGCCUAUGGAUGAACAUGUUUUACCAGAUGAUGCUGAUAUAAAUUUUGGAUACUGUGAAGUGGAAGAAAAAUGUAGACAGUCUUUUGAGGCUUGGCAAGAGAAACAGAAGGAAUUAGAAGAUAAAGAGAAACAAACUCUCAAAGCUCAGAGGGAUAGAGAAGAAAAACAAUUUCAAGAAGAAGAAGAAAAGCGACAUUGCUGGAUGAAACAAUUUAAAGUUGAAAAGAAGAAAUUAGAGAACAUUCAGAAGCAAGAACAGGACAAGAUGAAUGAUGAACUCUAUAAAGAAGAGAAAAUUUGGAAAGAGAAAUUUAAACAGCAUGAGGAGUAUAUUAGAAACUUGCAUUUACAAAUGGAAGAAGAAAGAACAAGAUUUAAAGACCAACAAGAAAAAGAAAAAAAUUCUUUGUUAAAACAGCAGAAUAAUGCAGCUGUUAAAAUUCAAGCUAAAUAUAAAGCAUUUGUUGCCUAUCAAAAAUAUGGCCCAAUUAUUAAAGAGCAAAUUGAAAGUAAGAAAAGGAAAGCACAAGAGUGGAAGGAAAAGGAAGCAAAAAUACGACAAAAGGAGGAAGAAAAUCGAAAAAGAUUAGAGGAGGAACAAAGGAUAAAAGAAGAGAGAAAAAAGCAAAAGGAAGAGGAAAGGAAAAGGAGAGAAAAAGAAUAUGAAGAAAAAAAGAAUAUUGUGAAACAGGAAAGAGAGCAACUAAUAAGCAAGGAAAAAAUAAUAUUAAGAGAAGAUGCAAGCCAACAGCUAAUAAUAAGUAGUGCAUUAAAGAAGAGCGGAUAUAAUAACAAACAUUUAAGUCUUGAAGAUAUUUCAAAUGAUAAGGGUGAUAUAGCCAAAAAUCUAGUGGAUGAAAAUUCAAAGAAGCAGGAAGAUGUUCUCCUUUGGCUAGUUGAGGAAUCAAAUAUGAAAGAAAAUGUAGAUAGACAGACUAUAUUAAAAGAAUCAAUACAAGUAAAGUUAAAAGAAUCUAUAUCAAGCCAAACAAUUCUGGCAGAUUUUAAAAUGGAAGAAAAAAAUGAAAACCUAGCAAAAAAACGAUGUUCAGAAGAAUUGGUCAAGCAAGAAAGAAAAUAUGAAAAUACAGAUAACAAAACUGAAUUGGGAAACUCUGAUCUAAAAGGAAAUCUGAAAGAACAGUUUCCAUUGCAAGAAUUAAAGUCUGAUGCACAAAAAGAAGAAAAAAUCAUGAAACAUGUCAUAAAUGAGAAUACAGGACAAAAAACCCAGAUAAUAUUAGGACAUAACCAAGAAAUCAGUGAGGUGAAAACCAAUGAAGAGCAGAAAAUAAUCAAAGAUAAUCAGCAGAAAAAGAUACAAAAAGUAGAAAAAGAAGAGAUACAAGAACAGAAUGGAUUAUUAUAUAAAGAUAAGGAUACUUUAGUUAUUUCAGUGAAACAAAGAUCACUCUCACUAACAUCAGAAAAUUCCAAAGAUGUAAGAGAAAACGUAAUAUUACAAGAAAAAGAAAUUUAUUCAAAAUCCAAAGAAAUUGAGGAGAACCCAAAAGACAAUGCUUGGAAUAGUGGCAUUGUGAUUUUUAACACAACUGAUACCAUGAUAAAUAUAGAAGGCAAAAGAAAUGACCAAGAUUAUGUGUUAGGUAGACAUGCUCCUUGUGAGGGCUUGAGUAACUAUAAUGCAGAAAGCUCCAUGGUAUCUAAAGAAGUCAACUCUCUUAAAUCUGAGAUUAGAAAUAUUUCAGAAAAAUGCCAUGAAAAUGCACCUGAACCUGAUAGCAUGACCUGCUGUGUAUCAGAGUCAACCCUUCUAUAUUCUAUUGAAGAAAGGAGACUAGCCUGGAUAAAAUCAUUUAAACCUUGGCUUGAAAUUUUCAAGCAAAAUCAACAAAAGAAAAUUGUUAGAAGAAAGAGACCUGUGAAAUGCCCAGCCAACAUGACACCCGCUUUGGAUAAACUGGAAAUUCUUCGAUGUGGCCCUUGGGAUACUUUACAGCAGGUUACAACAGUUACAUUUCAAGAUUUGCCAGGCUGUGUUCUCUCCACACUGGCAGAGUGUACAAAUCUUCAGUUUCUAUCCCUUCGACGCUGUGGAUUAACUUCUUUGCACAGCCUGAGUAAUUGUAAAAAACUUAAGUACAUUGAUGCACAGGAAAACCAUAUUGAGGCUAUUGAGUGUGAAAAUUUGGAAAAUCUCUGUGUUGUUCUUCUUAAUAAAAAUCAACUGACUUCUCUUCAUGGUUUGGAUGGCUGUACUAAUAUUCAGUGUCUUGAACUUUCAUAUAAUAAAAUUACUCGAAUUGGAUAUUCCUUCUUUCUGGAAGAAAAACUUGUUGACAAUGCAGGGUUCUGCCAUCACUUGGGCACCUCCACUUCUUACUUAUCCCUGGCACAAGUCUGGAUUCCAACUGGAUUAUGUUGGUCCUGGAUACCUAUUACCUCACUUACAAAAAAUUCAGAUUGUAAUUUCCUUAUCUCCCACUUAUACUGGAAUUGUGGUUUAGAAUCUUUGAAAAAUCUUCAACAACUAAUUUUGGACCACAAUCAGUUAAUUAAUACAAAAGGUCUUUGUGAUACACCUACCAUUGUAUACCUAGAUUGCUCCCAUAAUCAUCUUACUGAUGUAGAGGGCGUUGAAAAUUGUGGAUUGCUCCAAAUAUUGAAGUUACAGGGAAAUUAUCUGAGUGAGCUUCCAUCCUUGGAGAAUCUUGUUUUACUAAGAGAAUUGCACUUGGAUGAUAACAGCAUUUCAACUGUGGAAGCAUUUUCUUCAUACUGGCUGCCUUUACUACAAAAUAUUACUAUCUCUCAAAACAGCUUGACUAAAAUCGUACCACUUUUUCAUUUUGUUUCAUUGGAAAAGCUAGAUGUCAGCCACAAUUGUCUUUCUGAUCUUAAAAGUGCCAUAAAAUGGUUUGAUGCAUGCUAUUCUCUCCAUGAAUUGUCUCUUACUGGAAACCCACUUCUUCAAGAAACAAACUGGAGGGAUUCUCUACUUAAAGUGUUGCCUGCUCUGAGAAUCCUCAAUGGCAAUAUACUAAACUCUAAUUCAGAAAGCCGCACUGAAGAACACAAUCAACUGGGAUCAGCAGGUUUCCUGGCACUUUGUCAGUCUCAGAUUCGAGAAUUCAACUUGCUAAUUGAAAAUUAUAUAACUGGAAAAGGAGAUGUAUUUACCUUGGAUACUGCAGAAAAUCUCUGUCAUUAUUUUAAGAAAUUGAUGAUACUUAGUACUGAAUACCGACAUGCACACGAACGAGGGGAUGUAACUAUCACCAAGAAAGAUGAAUCAGAAGCCCAGAAAAAUCAUUUGGCCCCUACAAACAGUGACAGCACUCUGCAAAAUGGAGUCUUCUACUCUUGUGCACGUGAAGGUGAGCCAGACUCACCAGAUAUUCCUGAGAAAUGGAUGGACUCUGUCUCCAGCCACUCCCCAUUAAGCAAAUCCGCCACAUGUGAAAAUAUGGAAGGAAGACAUCAGGAAAUAUUAGUAUGUCAGAAGAGAGAAGACAGCAAGGCAAGCAGUAUUCCCACCAUAAGAAUCCCAUUUAAGGAAGUAGUAAUGACAAAUUCUUUGCUGAGGAAUCACCAAAAUAUUGAGCCUAGUGAAAAAAUUAUGGCAGCUGUGGUAAUCCAGUCAUACUGGCGUGGUUACCUCAUGCGCAGACAGACUCAUUUCUCCACAAGGCUACAUACUGCUGCAACAGAAGGCCUGCCAAAUUCUUCCAUCAAGAAUCAGACUAUUUUAAAGAAAGGAAAAAGAGAAAAUAUUGUGAAUAUCCGAAAACAGAGGGAGAAGGCUGCUAUUCUUAUUCAGGCAGUUUGGAAGGGCUUUAUUUUGCGAAAGAAACUGACAACAGCUCUAGAGGCUAUUAAGAAUGAAGAAUCCGAUGAAGAAUACAGAGAAAUAGAUUUAGAGGAUUUUAUAUUUGAUGAAGCUGCCUUAGAAGAAGAAUGGCUAGCAUUAGAUUCCACCCGCUUCCCUUCACAAACACUGCUUCUUUCAAACCAGCUGCAUUGGCCAAAGAUUCCUGGAAACUUAAAAUGGGAUGAUACUUCAUUUAAUUUACCAAGUAAUCCAGCUCAAGCAUGGUUAUGUAAUGACAAAGAAAAUUUGUCUUCUUCAGAACACACACAAUUUAAUAGCAGAUCAGAAAAUAAAACUUCUUCCUGGACACCUGAAUCAAAGACCAGUAGAAAGAGUUUGCUAAAAUCUGAAAAAGAAAAAAAAAUUUCAGAAGAAUGGGGCUUUAAGGAUAUUUCUACUGCUCAGCAAAUGUUGAAGAGGGCACAGAAAAUGAAAUCGAAGAAACUAAAGAAAAAAAUAGAUUCCACUGUGCGUCUAGCCUUAUUCAAAAACAAUGAAAAUAAAGUGUCUCUUCCAAAAUCACCAAAGAUGGUACAGCCCAGAAGAGAUGGUUACUUUGAAGGGGAAAACAGUGACGAAAAGUGAGGCAAAAUCAUUUGUUCAUUGCUGGCCAAGUUGAACCCCAUGUUGUCUUUAACUGCUGCUCUGGAAUUAUUCACUUCACAGAAUCACAGAUAUUUCCUGAUGCCACAGAGUGCAGCUUCCAAAGAAAUAUCCCAACUUACCCCUACUGCCCAGUAGAGAGUGCCUCCUGAACCCAAUUCUUCUGAGAUACAACUUUAUUAUAAAAUGCACCUCUUUUAAAAGUGCAAUACAAUGAACUCUACUAUAUUUACAGUUACAUAACCAUCACCAAAUCUAGUUUUAGAACAUUGGAAGAUCUUUUAUUCCUUAAGAAAAAAAAUCAAAUAAAAUUAGUGGUUGGGCAUCUGAUGCCCCCCAGAAAAGUGAGGAAGAUCAAAAUUAAAUUUUCCUGUAGGUUCAUAUUGAAUAAUUCCAUGUGGAACAGUAUCUCAGCACAAUGGUAUGCCAACACUGUCUUAUAAUUUCCUUGGUUUUGUUGAAAUUGGAUCAUACUGUAGAACUGCUUGACUAUUGCUUUCCAAAAUCCACAUUUAUUUUAGUAACAUUGUAUAAAUUUAAAAAAAAAUUACUUUCUAUCUCCACUCUGCAAUGUUGACUAUAUGGGGUUUCCAUGAUUCUUCUUACAAAUUUGAUUUUUAUUGUGGCUUUUUCUGAACAUCCCUAGCAAAAACAUUAGUAGCAAGAAAGGAUGGUAGAUAUAUCUCUGUUGGUCUAUGAUUAAAAAUAUGCUUAAAUUCAAGGAAUAGUUGAUAUUAAAUAUCAAAUUAUAUUAAAAAUAUAAGGUAAAAUAUUAUACCAUUUUUACAGUCUAUGUUUUACAGGAUGUUCUUCUAUUUUUUCUAUAUUCAUAAAAUGUUGACCAUUUUUGUCUGGCUACCAGAUUUAGAUCUUUAACUUAAUCAAGUCUGAGGAGCCUUUGACCACGCCUGUCCCCAGAGUCACCUCAUAUAUGUGCCAUGUGUCACCUAUUAGCCAGUUUUUCCUAUGAGACAAGUCUGAGAGCCUGAACACUUUGCAGAUUUAACAUUGGCUUAUUUUAUUUAUUUGUUUAUUUAUAUUUAUUUUGAAUCAGAUGCCUGUCUUUGUUUACCUUUGUUACCAACCUGUAAUACCUACUUGGAUUUCAAUAUCCUAUAUUGUCUUAGAACUCAAAACAAUUUCUUGGUUAUUGCCUUAAAGAUCUGCAGCCAAGUUUCUUUUUUUUCUGUCUUAAUUGUUUAGUUUGGAGCUCUGACAUCAUUUAUAUUCAUCACUUGCAUAAGAACAAGCAUAGCUUAAUGGACAUUAGUGUAGAUUCUGGAGUUAGUCCAACACAGUUUGAAUCUUGUCUUUAUCGUUUAUUAGCUCUGUGACCUUUGGGAAGUUGUUUAACUUCUCUGUUUCUCAUUAUUUUUCAUCUAUGAAAUAAGAGGCGAACAGUACUUAGGCAUGGGGAGUAUUGUGAGGAUUACAUAGAUUUUAUUUGUGAGAAUCUUGGAACACACAAUCUAAGUACAUAUUAAGUGCUCAAAAUGUAAUCAUUAGCAAUAGUCAUUUUAAAAGUAUGGCAUCCCUUCUUGUUCUUGUUUACAAUUAGUUCUCUUUAUUCCAUUUAUUAUUAAGUACUGUGCUGAGAGUUUUACUUACGUUCUCUGAUUCAGUGCUUUCAGAAACUUUGAGAAAGGUAUUAUGACUGUCAACAUUUUACAGAUGAUAAAACAGUAGUAUUGAGAGAUUGAUAGGUGACUUGACCAAGGUUUCUACAUAGAAAACAAGUGGCUGAAGGGAAAUGGUAAUAAUUUCUUUGACAAAUAAAGCUUGCAAAAUCAAAACAAAAUACAAAUGUUAGAGAAAAAAGAUUACCAGGUAACCAUGAAAUUUAUACCACUUAGAAUUAAAAUACUUAGGAAAAAAGUAAAGACUAAUUAUUAAAAUAAGGUAAAACUCUGAGAAAACCAUAAUCAAUUUUGGUUUUUAUUCCUUUCUCAUAGUUGCAUUAAUAUAAUUUAGGAUAUCAUUUAGUGCCAACAUGGUAAUGAAGAUUUGAUUUGUGACCUAUAGUUAGCUGCUAUCUUGGAUAAUGUUAUUAUUGAUAUUAUUAUGAUAACCUAAUAUUAAAUAUCAAGUCUGUGAGAUUAUUAGUAAAGAGUGACCAUUUUUAAAAUAAUUCCAACUUUUAUUUUAGAUUCAGGGGUAACAUGGGCAGUUUUGUUAAAUUGUGUAUGAUACUGAGGUUUGGGCUACAAAUGAUCUCAUCACCCAGAUAAAGAGCAUAGUAACAAACAGGUACCGUUUUUCAGCCCCUGGUUUCCUCCCUCUCUCCCCACUCUAGUAGUUCCUGGGGUCUAUUGUUUCUGUCUUUGCGUCCAUGUGUACCUGAUGUUUAGCUCCCACUUAUAAGUGAGAACAUGCGGUAUUUGGUUUUCUGUUCCUGCAUUAAUUGCCUUAAGAUAGUGGCCUCCAUGUUGCUGGAAAGGACAUGAUUUCUUACUUUUUUUUUUUUUUUUUUUUUUUGAGACAGAGUCUUGCUCUGUCACCCAGGCUCAAGUGCAGUGACACUAUCUCUUCUCACUGCAACCUCUGCCUCCCAGGUUCAAGCAAUUCUCCUGCCUCAUCCUCCCAAGUAGCUGGCAUUACAGGCACACGCCACCACGCCCAGCUAAUUUCUUUUGUAUUUUAGUAGAGACGGGGUUUCACCGUGUUGCCCAGGUUGGUCUCCUGAGCUCAGGCAAUCCACCCGCCUUGGCCUCCCAAAGUGCUAGGAUUACAGGCAUGAGCCACCGCGCCCGGCUGAUUUGAUGCAUUUUAAUGGCUCCAUAGUAUUCCAUGGUAUAUAUGUUCCACAUUUUCUUUAUCCAAACCACUGCUGACGAGCACCUAGGUUGAUUUCAGGUCCCUGCUAUUGUGACUAGUGCCGCGAUGUACAUACGAGUGCAUGUCUUUUUGGUAGAAGGAUUUAUUUUCCUUUGGGUUUAUACCCAGUAAUAGGAUUGCUGUGUCGAAUGGUAGUUCUAUUUUCAGUUCUUUGAGAAAUCUCCCACAUUUUGAAUCACAUGUUUUAAUUUUCAGAUAUAUGAGAACCUCCCCACAGAGCCUAUAUUUUUGCUUCAUUAUUCCUAUUUUUAUUUAUACAUAAAUUAAGUCACUUUCCUGCCCUCAUCUACUGAAACUUCUAAAUUUGCUACUUCUAAAGUCAAUGCCAAAUUCAGACUUCUGGCUUUGGUCAGGGAAGGAAGUUAGCCAAGCCAGGAAAAAAAUUUAGUCUGGCGCAACAACUUUCUGAGGAAUACGGGUUUAUUUAGUCUUAGCUCCUCCAUUCCCUGGGACAAUUGUACUCGAUUUCAAGUCAGAUUUUCUUAAUUCCCAGUCUGCUGCUGUCAUCACUAACAUGCUUCCUAUUUGUUCUUUUAUAAAAUAGAAGAUUUGCAGAUAACUCAUGGUUUUAUAAACAUAUAUUCAAAUAUUUUUGUAUUAAAUGUUUAAAUAUUGAAUGUAUUAAGAAACCUAUAACUUCUAUAAUUUUUACUCCAGAACAUUUCUUUUGUGAUACUUUUUACUUUAGAAUUAUAAGCAUUUUCUCCUCCUGACUUCUCCUUUUUAAUGCCAGCUUAGAGAACAGUUUAUGUUGUGUAGAUUGCUUUAAAGGAGGUCUUGCAUUUCCCUAGCUGUUUAUAGUACUUGCUAAUAGUGCCAAUGACUAUGUAUUAAGAGAUGGCAGCAUAAAUGCCACAGGGCAUAUGCAGGCAACAAAAUACCUGAAGGCAGCCCCGUAAGAAGAGAUGCUCAUAAUUUUAUUCCACUGAGCAAGAUUCAAUAAUUAGUCAAAAUUAUCAUGGAUGCAAAGAUUUAUAAAAUGUGAUUUAUCAGUAUGUCAGUCUCCAACAAACACUAUAUUUUGAAUUACUGUUUUCCUACUAAGUUUUGAGCUCCAUGUAUUUCUUUAAUACCCCUAGCCCUUAGCACAGUGCCUAAUGUAUAAUGGAUAGUUAAUAAAUGUUUUUUGAUGAAUAACUGAAAAAUACAAAGGACCCUGGCAUUAAAGAGUGUCAAACAUAGAUGGAGUUGCAAUAUGCUUAUAUAAUAUUUUUUAACAUGCUGUUUGCUUUGCCAAAUUAGACUCAUUGCCCUAUGCAAUCCAGAAAAAUCUCUUCACUUGGCUAAUUUGUAUUAUCUCAGGCAUUUAAUUUUUUAGGAAGACUUUUCUGAUUCUAGUUUAGAACACCACUCACUGUGUGUCCUGAAUAAACUUUUAUAUGCCAUAUGUAUUAUUAGUCAGGGUUCUCUAGAGGGACAAAACUAAUAGGAUAGAUGUAUAUAUAAAGGGAAUUUAUUAAAAAGUAUUGACUAACACGAUCACAGAGUGAAGCCCCACAAUAGGCCAUCUGCAAGCUGAGGAGCAAGGAAGCCAGCCCGAGUCUCAAAACCUCAAAAGUAGGGAAGCCAACAGUGCAGUCUUCAGUCGUUUGCUGAAGGCCCAAGUGCCUCUUGCAAACUGCUGGUGUAAGUCCAAGAGUCCAAAAGCUGAAGAACUUGGAGUCCAAUGUUCUAGGGCAGGAAGCAUUCAGCAUGGGAGAAAGAUGAAGGCUGGAAGACUCAGCAAGUCUCUCUUCCAUCUUCUCCUGCCUACUUAAUUCAAGCCAAGCUGGUAGCUGAUUAGAUGGUGCCCACCCAGAUUGAGGGUGGGCCUGCCUUUCCCUGUUUACUGACUCAAAUGUUAAUCUCCUUUGGCAACACCCUCACAGACACAACCAGGAACAAUACUUUGCAUUCUUCUAUCCAAUCAAGUUGACACCCAGUAUUAACCAUCACAAGUCCACCCCUUGUCAACUUGAACCCAUUCACAUGUCCUGACAUCACACAUAAUCUUCAAAUAAAGACAAUAAUAAGGUCAUAAUAAUGCCUAACCUAACGCAGCUAGCAUUCAUACAAUCGGAAGUGCACUAAUCCUUAACCUAAAUGCUAUUACAUAAAGUUAACAACACUUAAAUCCUGUCAUGAAGUCAAUAAAUUUUAUGGCACAUUAUAAAGGAAAAAGAAAGGAA